AACUCCUGCCAGGCAGUGCCCUUCCCGGAGCGUGCCCUCGCCGCUGGUGAGUGAGGACGGGACGCGGAGGGGGCAGCGGGAAGUGGGGGCCCGCAUGGCUGCGACUCUUGGCAGCGCCGCGGGACAGAGGGAAACUGAGGCCGGAGCCGCAGACUGGACACCCGAGGGGGCGACCCGGGGCAGCACUUGGGGCUCGGCUACCGGGUCAGGGGGCGGCGGGCAGCAGAGUCUGGGCCUCCGCGGCCGGGGUUCCAGCGCGGGCCGCCUCCGGCUGGGGGUUCGGGAGGGAAAACUUGGACAACCCUGCCACGCCCAGCCCUUGGCCGCGUGGCUUCUCCUGCAGGAAGCGCGGUCCCAGGAGUGGCCGACGCUCCCUCUCCUGCCCAUUCCGCGGAUGGGCAAUCCCAGGCGGAACUCCCUUGAGGGUCUCAGAAUAUCUGGGAGACCUCGGGCUCUUGAUCUCCGAGACACCCCGUUUCGUAGUGGAGAACAGUCCAGAUCGGGGAAGUUUAUUUUGCCCAAAGCCGGUUAGAGGCCCCCUGGCCCUCGAUUCCCAGUGCGGGGCUCAGGUGCGUUGCAGCCUAGACGGGUCUUACUGUGAGCCGAGCAGCCUCUGGGACCUGUCUGCUUCCCCUACCCCUUGCAAAGAAGCCGGAGCCCAGGUAGGAGAAGCGGGGGCUUCCUGCUGUGAACGCGCUGCUGGCCAGGGCAGCUGCCAGAGGCCAUGGCCUGGCGUGGGCCUGGAGCCCCUCUGGCCAGCCUGCCAGGGGCCAGGGCUACGGGAUACCAGCAGCGUGCCCUGGGCUGGAUGGCAGGAGAGACAGGACUUGAGGCUGUCCCAGAAUGGGCUCAGGCAGGGCGAGGAUAUCAGGGGAGGUGGUGUACAGGAAGCAGCCGCCCAGCUUGCCUGGCACACAGCAAGCCCUGCCCAUGAAGGCCUACUGCCAGAACAGUGGGCGAGGCCCGGCGUCUCUGUGGAGUCGGUGGGGCCCGGGACAGGGCAGCCUGAGGCAGGUUUCCACUGGCGGUGAAAGGGGCCGUGUGGCAAGGACAGGAGAGCCAGCCUCAGCCCAGCAGGGGAAGGCGGCCCCUGAGUCUCCACCUGGCUGCUGGCAGCCCCACAGGGAGGUUCGGCGAAACUGAGGCUUGCCAAAGAAGCCUUUGUCCAGAGUCACGCAGCUGGCGCGGUGGAGCCAGGGCCAGAACCCGUGCAGGCUGAUCCCAGCCUGCCUUCUCCACUGUGCCCCGAGGACCACUUUCUUUCCUGGGAGUGUGUGUGUGCACAUGUGCUGUGUCCUGUCGUCUGUACACACUUGUGCCUGGCGUGAGGCAGGAUGUCUGGCUGGAUCUACCAGAAAGUAUUCACAGCGGGUUCUCCAGCUGGGGUGAGGGGCUUGGGCUCGCAGGGAGGGAGCCUACUUUUCACUUUAGCUUGCUUUCUUCCUUUCUUCCGUCCUUCCUUCCUCCCUCCCUCCCCUCCCCUUCCCACCCCUUCUUUCUCUUUCUUCUUUCUCUUUCUUUCUUUCUUUCCUUCCUUCCUUCUUUCCUUUCUCUUUCUCUUUUUUUCUUUCUUCCCCUUCCUUCCUUCCUUUCUUGUUUUUGUUUGUUUGUUUGAGACAGGGUCUCACUCUGGUAUGCAGGCUGGAGUGCAGUGAUGCAAUCAUAGCUCACUGCAGUCUCCUGCAGAACUCCUGGGCUCAAGCGAUCCUCCCACCUCAGCCUCCCAAAGUGCUGGGAUUACAGGCAUGAGCCACUGUUCCUGGCUUAUUUGUGUUUUCUUUUUUUUUUUUUUUUUUUUUUUUUUGAGACGGAGUCUCGCUCUGUCGCCCAGGCCGGACUGCGGACUGCAGUGGCGCAAUCUCGGCUCACUGCAAGCUCCGCUUCCCGGGUUCACGCCAUUCUCCUGCCUCAGCCUCCCGAGUAGCUGGGACUACAGGCGCCUGCCACCGCGCCCGGCUAAUUUUUUGUAUUUUUAGUAGAGACGGGGUUUCACCUUGUUAGCCAGGAUGGUCUCGAUCUCCUGACCUCAUGAUCCACCCGCCUCGGCCUCCCAAAGUGCUGGGAUUACAGGCGUGAGCCACCGCGCCCGGCUUAUUUGUGUUUUCUUUACUUUUGAUGGUGCAAACAAUGCUUGGAUGUGCUCUCUGUUUAAAACGGUAGUCUUUUUUAUUUUUUUUUUUAACCACUAGACCACUAGGGAAGUCAUUCUUAAUUUCUUAUUUUUAUUUAUAUAUAUAUUUUUUGAGACGGUGUCUCGCUCCAUUGCCCAGGCUGGAGUGCAGUGGCUCCAGCUGGGCUCACUGCAACCUCCGCCUCCAGAGUUGAAGUGAUUCUCCUGCCUCAGCCUGGCUAAUUUUUAUAUUUUUAGUAGAGAUGGGUUUCACCAUGUCGGCCAGGCUGUUUCUUUAUUUUUUACUAAAAAAAAGUUUAACCCCCGAACCUCGAAGGAAAGGGAAGUAGUCUUUCUUAACAGAACCAAUUCCCCCUGGAUACCCCACCCUCACCCUACCCUCUCCCAGGCCACUCGAUGGCCAGGUUCGCUGUGGAUUUUUCCAGACCUGUGGGCUGUUUCACUGGUUACUUUUGUAAUGAAAAAUGCACACAAAGGUUACGAUGAGGACGAUUAGCCAUGAAUCAUUUUUAAAAAGCCUGAAAACAAGUCCCUGGGACAGUGCUGGCUUCGUUGGAGAGACAAGGCUCAGGGGAGUGGGUGCAGCUGGGGGUCGGGGUGGGGAUCAGAGAAGGGACACAUUCCUUAUUGUGUUUCUGGGUCGCCUUCUUUUUUUUUGUUUGCUUUAUUUAUUUAUUUAUUUAUUUUGAGACAGAGUCUUGCUCUGUUGCCCAGGCUGGAGUGCAGUGGCGUAAUCUUGGCUCACUGCAACCUCCUCCUCUCGGGUUCAAGCAAUUCUCUUGCCUUAGCCUUCUGAGUAGCUGGGAUUACAGACGUGCGCCACCACACCAGGCUAGUUUUUUAUUUUUAGUAGAGACGGGGUCUCACCAUGUUGGCCAGGCUGGUCUCGAACUCCUGACCUGAGGUGAUCUGCCUGCCUCAGCCUCCCAAAGUGCUGAGAUUACAGGUGUGAGCCACCGUUCCUGGCCUUCUGGGUCACCUAUAGGGAGGUCUCCAAGAACAGAAAGACACCCUGAAACCCACUGGCUCGACCACCACCUCAUAGAUGGGGACACAGAGGCUCAGGAGAUGAGAUACCUUGGGGCAGCGAUGGGUCUGGGGUCUUCGGGCCAGGAGUGAAGCCUCACAAGACCUGGAGACCCUGGGUCCCACCCUCAGUGGGGAAGGGCUCAGAUUCUGCAGGGCCCGAUGCUCUGUGGGGGCUGGGAUGUUGCCGCGGCAGGUGGAGAGAGUGAUGCUACUGGCCCUGAGAGAACCUUCUGGCACCGUUCAGAGGUGGGGUGGAGUGGCCUGCGGGUCCAAUCCUGGCGCCGCAGGCUCUAUGAGCCCUGUUUCAGAUGAGGAAGGAGGCUGAGACGGGCGGUGACACAACUCCUGGCAAGUGGUCACGCGGCCCAGAGCAGCCCGGCAGACACCCAGCUCAAAGGGAGGGGUGGGGUGGGUUUUGGAGUCACUCGGACCUAGAAAGUUCUGUGACUUCUCAUGUCUCAGUUUCCUCAUCUGGAAAAUGGGACCAGUCACGAGUCCACCAUGGAGGCCGAGUGGGCCGUGUGGCUCAGGGAGAAGCAGCUGGUCCCCUGUGGCUGCUGUGGGGACUGAACAAGGCGGUGACCGUCGGGAUGAGCACGGACUCCACCACGCAGGCCCCUGCCUACCAGAGGCCUGUGCACAACCAGAGCUGAGCAAGGCUUGGAACCUUCUCCUGCCUCUACGUCCUGCGCCCUCUACCCUGCCCCGAUCUUGCCCCUGUUUUGGGGGCGCUGCUCCGUGCAGGGCAUUUUCACCUGUGGAGUGUCCAGGGGCUCUCGUGGCUGAUAAGGUCUCGUCACAGGUCCAAGCCUUGAGGCCCUGUCUUCCCCUGGAGGAAAUGGGGCUAGUGGCCCCACACUGAUACCCACAACCCCUCUCUUCUCUGGAGUUUUCAGGGAAACGUUGUUGUCCCACCCCUUCCUCCCUUGAGCUACCCCAGCCCCCCAAGAAGCAGACACAGCGGGUUUACCCACCUGACGUUGGAGGAAGCCAGGCCCAGAGACGAGCCUUGGAUGGAGGCAGAGCCGAGGUCUGGAUCCCGAUUCGCUUUCUGAAGGAGACAAAUAAAGGGUGUAUAGGUGGCUUCACCCCUCUGCCUGAGCCUGAGUCCUGUCCCUGCCAUGUGUGCCCCCUGGCCUGGCCCACCCCAGCUUUCCCUGGACUCAUCCCAGAGCAGAUAUCUGGAUCCUGCCUAGCCUGGCUCAGCAUGACUCAUCAUGAGCUCCCCUGAACAGCAGCUGCAGCAGCCAUGGCCCCGCCCUGGGUGCCCGCCAUGGGCUUCACGCUGGCGCCCAGCCUGGGGUGCUUCGUGGGCUCCCGCUUUGUCCACGGCGAGGGUCUCCGCUGGUACGCCGGCCUGCAGAAGCCCUCGUGGCACCCGCCCCACUGGGUGCUGGGCCCUGUCUGGGGCACGCUCUACUCAGCCAUGGGGUACGGCUCCUACCUGGUCUGGAAAGAGCUGGGAGGCUUCACAGAGAAGGCUGUGGUUCCCCUGGGCCUCUACACUGGGCAGCUGGCCCUGAACUGGGCAUGGCCCCCCAUCUUCUUUGGUGCCCGACAAAUGGGCUGGGCCUUGGUGGAUCUCCUGCUGGUCAGUGGGGCGGCGGCAGCCACUACCGUGGCCUGGUACCAGGUGAGCCCGCUGGCCGCCCGCCUGCUCUACCCCUACCUGGCCUGGCUGGCCUUCACGACCACACUCAACUACUGCGUAUGGCGGGACAACCAUGGCUGGCGUGGGGGACGGCGGCUGCCAGAGUGAGUGCCCGGCCCACCAGGGACUGCAGCUGCACCAGCAGGUGCCAUCACGCUUGUGAUGUGGUGGCCGUCACGCUUUCAUGACCACUGGGCCUGCUAGUCUGUCAGGGCCUUGGCCCAGGGGUCAGCAGAGCUUCAGAGGUGGCCCCACCUGAGCCCCCACCCGGGAGCAGUGUCCUGUGCUUUCUGCAUGCUUAGAGCAUGUUCUUGGAACAUGGAAUUUUAUAAGCUGAAUAAAGUUUUUGACUUCCUUUA